ACUUGCAUUUCUCUUUAGGUUGUGGACGAAGUGUUUAUUUAUCAUGCCUGAACCUGCUAAGUCCGCUCCUGCUCCAAAAAAGGGCUCCAAAAAGGCGGUGACCAAGGCGCAGAAGAAGGAUGGUAAGAAGCGCAAGCGUAGCCGCAAGGAGAGCUAUUCCGUGUACGUGUACAAGGUGCUAAAGCAGGUCCACCCCGACACCGGCAUCUCAUCCAAGGCCAUGGGCAUCAUGAACUCCUUCGUCAACGAUAUCUUCGAGCGCAUCGCUGGCGAGGCUUCCCGCCUGGCGCAUUACAACAAGCGCUCCACCAUCACCUCCAGGGAGAUCCAGACGGCCGUACGCCUGCUGCUGCCCGGGGAGCUGGCUAAGCACGCCGUGUCAGAGGGCACCAAGGCCGUCACCAAGUACACCAGCUCUAAGUAAUUCUAACGUCUUCAUACCCAAUCCCAAAGGCUCUUUUAAGAGCCACCCA